GACCGGGUCGGUCCGUCGCCAUUUUGUUGGUUGGUUUUUUUUUAAACCCUUUCGCUUCCCGCCCGAAUAAUAAUAAAAAGCCCCAUUGGAGUGAGGCGGGGGUGGCGGCGGCAACCGCGGCGGGGGUAUCCGGGGAGACUGCUGCUGUCGCUGCUGCUGAUCGCGGCCCAGGUCGGCCUCAGAGAGCGGACACCCCGAGCGGGGGGUGCGGGCGCCGCCGCCGCCGCUUCUGCUGCUGCUGUUCCUGCUGCUGCUGUUGGUGCCGCUGCCGCCGCCGGCGAGCAGGCGGGACCGGUGUGAGUGCGAGUGUGUGUGCGAGGGAGCGUGUGCGAGGGCGAUUGUGCGCGCGAGUGUGCGGGUGUGUGCGAGUGUCUGUCUGUCUGUGCGGGGACUCGGGGGCGGGCGGUUCGGGCUCUCCUGGCGGAGGAGCCGCCGCCGCCGCCCGGGCCCCGGCGCUUCUCGCUGCGCAGGUUCGGAGCGCGCGCCAUUUUGUGAGAUUUACAAAAUCCUCCUCGGGAAGAAGCCGCCGGCAGCAGCCGCCGCUCGGCGCCCGGCCUCGCCGACGCCGCCCUCUGCGCCGGGCCGGCCGUGCGGCCCCGCCGCCUGGAAUCGGGGCCCGGGGACUGCGGUAUUUGCCGGGGAGGGGGCUGUCGCCUCCCCGGCCCCGGGCGCCGCUGGAACCGCGAGCCGAGGAGAGACUGAGCAGGCUGCGGCGCGGCCAGGAGCCGGAGCGCCGGGGGCGGAGAGAGGCUGCCGGGGCGGCGCUGGCUGCGGAGGCCGCGGCGGGAGCGCGGCGCGGGAGCCCGAGGCUGAGACUCACCGGAGGAAGCGGCGCGAGCGCCCCGCCAUCGUCCCGUGUUAUAGUUUUGCCGCUGGACUCUUCCCUCCCUUCCCCCACCCCAUCAGGAUGAUAUGAGACUUGAAAGAAGACGAUGCAUACAGGAGGAGAGACUUCAGCAUGCAAACCUUCAUCUGUUCGGCUUGCACCGUCAUUUUCAUUCCAUGCUGCUGGCCUUCAGAUGGCUGGACAGAUGCCCCAUUCACAUCAGUACAGUGACCGUCGCCAGCCAAACAUAAGUGACCAACAGGUUUCUGCCUUAUCAUAUUCUGACCAGAUUCAGCAACCUCUAACUAACCAGAGGCGGAUGCCCCAAACCUUCCGUGACCCAGCAACUGCUCCCCUGAGAAAACUUUCUGUUGACUUGAUCAAAACAUACAAGCAUAUUAAUGAGGUUUACUAUGCAAAAAAGAAGCGAAGACACCAACAGGGCCAGGGAGACGAUUCUAGUCAUAAGAAGGAACGGAAGGUUUACAAUGAUGGUUAUGAUGAUGAUAACUAUGAUUAUAUUGUAAAAAACGGAGAAAAGUGGAUGGAUCGUUACGAAAUUGACUCCUUGAUAGGCAAAGGUUCCUUUGGACAGGUUGUAAAGGCAUAUGAUCGUGUGGAGCAAGAAUGGGUUGCCAUUAAAAUAAUAAAGAACAAGAAGGCUUUUCUGAAUCAAGCACAGAUAGAAGUGCGACUUCUUGAGCUCAUGAACAAACAUGACACUGAAAUGAAAUACUACAUAGUGCAUUUGAAACGCCACUUUAUGUUUCGAAACCAUCUCUGUUUAGUUUUUGAAAUGCUGUCCUACAACCUCUAUGACUUGCUGAGAAACACCAAUUUCCGAGGGGUCUCUUUGAACCUAACACGAAAGUUUGCGCAACAGAUGUGCACUGCACUGCUUUUCCUUGCGACUCCAGAACUUAGUAUCAUUCACUGUGAUCUAAAACCUGAAAAUAUCCUUCUUUGUAACCCCAAACGCAGUGCAAUCAAGAUAGUUGACUUUGGCAGUUCUUGUCAGUUGGGGCAGAGGAUAUACCAGUAUAUUCAGAGUCGCUUUUAUCGGUCUCCAGAGGUGCUACUGGGAAUGCCUUAUGACCUUGCCAUUGAUAUGUGGUCCCUCGGGUGUAUUUUGGUUGAAAUGCACACUGGAGAACCUCUGUUCAGUGGUGCCAAUGAGGUAGAUCAGAUGAAUAAAAUAGUGGAAGUUCUGGGUAUUCCACCUGCUCAUAUUCUUGACCAAGCACCAAAAGCAAGAAAGUUCUUUGAGAAGUUGCCAGAUGGCACUUGGAACUUAAAGAAGACCAAAGAUGGAAAACGGGAGUACAAACCACCAGGAACCCGUAAACUUCAUAACAUUCUUGGAGUGGAAACAGGAGGACCUGGUGGGCGACGUGCUGGGGAGUCAGGUCAUACGGUCGCUGACUACUUGAAGUUCAAAGACCUCAUUUUAAGGAUGCUUGAUUAUGACCCCAAAACUCGAAUUCAACCUUAUUAUGCUCUGCAGCACAGUUUCUUCAAGAAAACAGCUGAUGAAGGUACAAAUACAAGUAAUAGUGUAUCUACAAGCCCCGCCAUGGAGCAGUCUCAGUCUUCGGGCACCACCUCCAGUACAUCGUCAAGCUCAGGUGGCUCAUCGGGGACAAGCAACAGUGGGAGAGCCCGGUCGGAUCCGACGCACCAGCAUCGGCACAGUGGUGGGCACUUCACAGCUGCCGUGCAGGCCAUGGACUGCGAGACACACAGUCCCCAGGUGCGUCAGCAAUUUCCUGCUCCUCUUGGUUGGUCAGGCACUGAAGCUCCUACACAGGUCACUGUUGAAACUCAUCCUGUUCAAGAAACAACCUUUCAUGUAGCCCCUCAACAGAAUGCAUUGCAUCAUCACCAUGGUAACAGUUCCCAUCACCAUCACCACCACCACCACCAUCACCACCACCAUGGACAACAAGCCUUGGGUAACCGGACCAGGCCAAGGGUCUACAAUUCUCCAACGAAUAGCUCCUCUACCCAAGAUUCUAUGGAGGUUGGCCACAGUCACCACUCCAUGACAUCCCUGUCUUCCUCAACGACUUCUUCCUCGACAUCUUCCUCCUCUACUGGUAACCAAGGCAAUCAGGCCUACCAGAAUCGCCCAGUGGCUGCUAAUACCUUGGACUUUGGACAGAAUGGAGCUAUGGACGUUAAUUUGACCGUCUACUCCAAUCCCCGCCAAGAGACUGGCAUAGCUGGACAUCCAACAUACCAAUUUUCUGCUAAUACAGGUCCUGCACAUUACAUGACUGAAGGACAUCUGACAAUGAGGCAAGGGGCUGAUAGAGAAGAGUCCCCCAUGACAGGAGUUUGUGUGCAACAGAGUCCUGUAGCUAGCUCGUGACUACAUUGAAACUUGAGUUUGUUUCUUGUGUGUUUUUAUAGAAGUGGUGUUUUUUUUCCAAAAACAAAGUGCAAAGCUGCUUGAAUCAGGAGGAGAUUAACACACUGAACCGCUACAAGAGGGCAAAGCUGAUUUUUUUUUUAACUUGAAAAGAUUGCAAAGGGACAUUGAAGUGUUUAAAAGAGCCAUGUCCAAACCCAUCUUCAUGGAUAGCUCAGAGGUAUCCUCUUUUUGCUCCCCCAUUUUAACUUGCCACAUCCCAGUCACAGUGGGGUUUUUUUGUCUUUCUAUUCAGCAAAAGUUAAUAUUCAGAUGUUGGUCUUGGUCAUUUGCCAACUAAUUUUAAAGUAAAAGGCACUGCACAUAAUUUGCAUAAAGGGCCCCAUGAGGGUGUUUUUUUUUUUUCUUUUUGUCCCCCCCAUCCCCCUUUUUUUUUGUUUUGUUCUGUUUUGUUUUGGGUGGGAGGGUGGGAAAUUUGGGUUUUUAAGUCCUCUAAACACACUUGGGCACGGAAAUGCAGUACUGUAAGGAAGAGGGACCUCCAGCUUCCACAAACACCAUCUUCAGCUGUAUGAAAGGGACGGUUGUGGUGAAGUUUGUCAGGCACAGUAAGCAUGCUGAGUGGCGGGGAUCAGAACUCUCCUAUCUGAACCUACUGAGGAGCAAAGCAGCAAUUACAUGGGAUCCUGUGGCUCUCCCGUUGCAGAGGCCACAGGAAGAUAGGAUGGAACGUGACUGGUCUCCUAACCAAGGUGCACUGAGAAGCAAUCAACGGGUCGGUCGUGGCCAGUCCUGGGGAGGUCUGAGUGGUGGUCUUUGGGAUAACCUUUGGCCUUAUGGAUUUGGACUCGAAAUUAGAAGAGCCUACCAUUUCAGAUGCAAUCACUUUUGGACAUGCUUUUGCAGACAGUCCUUAAUGCUGAAAACACAGAGAAUGGGUAAUUCAAGAGGCCUUUCUUUUAAAAUAGACUUUUGUGACCCACUAAUUGUAAGGUAUUGCAAGGUCACUUUGCGUGUGUCAUAAAGUUGACUUCCUUAUUGGUUGAAGGUCACAGAAGUAGUGGUUUGCUUUGAUGGAAAUAGCUACAGCUGUGUCCCUUCCUGCUUUUUACUUUUUCUUUUGCUUUUUCUCGGCACGUGGUAUCUCCACCAUUUCUUCUGCACAAAGAUGUCUUCUGUUCAUCCUGAACAUUUUUAAAAAAUGCAGAAUUUUAUGUGACUGCUUUUUUGCCUCACAAUUAUGCUGUGAAUUUUACAAAAAUUUAUUUUCUUUUUUGAUAAUUUAUUGUACCAAAGCUGUUUUUAUAGCACAUAGAUGUCUGUAACCAAUAAUGUAGCAGUUCUGCACUUUGACACAAGGUGUAACUAGACCAUUUUUAAAUGUCAGUUGAAAAUUAUGGCUGUACUAUUGCUUAAACAAAACUGGAACUGUUGUUGAAUCCAUAGCCAAUACAUUUACAGCAAUCUGUGUACUGAACAUAGUAGAUUGACAUCUAAUUCAAGAUUACAACAUCUGUUACAUUCUAAGUGUGUUCAGGCUUCUGAAGGUAAAGGGACACUGGAUCCAGAAGCUAUGGAACCAGCAGUUGAUUCUUGUAUUCCUGAUUAACCUACUUGUAAACUUGAAAGCAAGACCUUGAUUGCACCAACAGGUCCAGAGUAUGAGUGCAAGCAAAGCAGAACUCUCAUGCGUGACCUGAGCAGACAGGCUGGUAUUUAACAGGUGCCUCGUGUUGAGAUUACGCUGCCUUAAUGUAACACAGUCUGGCAGUUGCUAAAUUUGUGUUCCCAUUUUAAAUUGACCAAUUUUGGGGUGUGACACUUUUGAGCGGUUGAAUUGGGAGAAUGAAGAUAAGUAAUUUACCUGUCCAGGAUCAAAAGAAGCCUAGAAAAGAAGCAGUAAUCUACCUCUGCCGAUAACCUGUUUAAGAUGACUCAGCAGAACACCGCGUUUCAUUCUAUUGGUCAAUUCCAUGUGGCUGACUAGGUCAAUUUUUUUUCUGAACAAAAGCAGGUUUUUAUAUGUAAACAGUGAGAAAAGAAAGGCUAAACACUAUGUAAAUGUGAAUGGAAACUUGGAAAUACUCGUUUUUAUAAACUACAAAAACUUUUUGUUGUUUAUCAGGAAAUCCAUAUUUAUUUUGUAAUUAACUGUCAAGCCUGUGGAUGAUUUUUUUGAACUUGGUAGUUCAUAAAGGUUUACAGUGAAUAAAAGGAUAUCAUCUUGAGUAUAGCAAUAUCAAAAGGAAUUCAGUAGUUACUGCUGUUUAGGAAUAUAAGGUUAAGAUAUCAUAUGGGUCAGGUCAUUUUUUUUUUCUGUGCUGGUUGCCACAUCUUAGCAAGCACCAAAAAACUAAAGCAGUUUUUAAACCGAUAUUUACGUAAAGAAAAUCAUAAAAUCCAAUGCUUCUGCAUACUGUGUUAUGUUACAGUCCAGUUUUGUGUGCUUUACUACACAGUUUGGUUACAGGACUUCUGUGCAUUGUAAACAUAAACAGCAUGGAAAAGGUUAAAUACCUGUGUUCAGAUUGUAAGAUCUAGUCCGGACUUGCUGUGUAUAUUGUAACGUUAAAUGAAAAAAGAACCCCCCUUUGUAUUAUAGUCAUGCGGUCUUAUGUAUGAUAAACAGUUGAAUAAUUUGUCCUCAGACUCUUUACUAUGCUUUUUUAAAAAUUAAUUUAAGAAAAAUGUAAACAUAGUAAAAAUCUUCCUAUGCAAUUAAACUGGUCCAGGUCUGGUAGGUAUAGUAUCAAAGUUGAGUUAAAUGUGUAAAAAGGAAACUAUUUGAGAUACAUUGACAUAGGCAUCAGCAAUCUCUGAAAGUAAAAAUUGGAGGUUUAACAGAUCAUUUUGAUUUUUCACAUUGAUUUUUUUAUUUGAAUGUUUACAUAAUUUUGUGAUUCAAAAUGCUCAUAUUUUAGUUGGUAGCAUUUCGACUGGAUGUGAGGGUCUGAUGGUUUUCUCUGAUAUGCUUUGACGUGCUUGGAUGAAGGAAGGAAUACGAAUACUCAUUCUUCCUUCCCUAACUCCUCGUACGGGGCCAUAUCAGAAUUCUAGAAUUCUUGCCACUGUGAUUCAAUUGCUAACCUAAAGUCUUCUCUUUUUACAAAUUCACCUGCUUCAGUAUAUAUUAAGGUGGCUUUCGAGAGGCAAGAUGCUUAUUUAAAAGUUAAGCGUGAAUCUGUAAAAUUAAGGUUGGUUGCGUAAAGUUGAAGUUAACCACAUGUAAGAAAGGAAAACUUCCAUUAGUUUUCUUCUUAGGGUGUGAGAAUUUUACCUAGGCACAUGGAUAUUGGGCUGAAAAAAAAAAACCGACAUUUUUAUUUAAAACUACAUGUAAAAAAUCAUGAAAGAUUCAGUAAUUAUGUUAGGCUCACAAGUGACCAUUGAGUUUGCCCCUGUACUGCUUCCCAGCUUUUGUGGUGUUGAACUUUUCUGUUCUUCCAAUAGGGAGAUACAUAAUCAAAAUACACACGAAGACGAGAUAGCAGGCACUCAGUUCUAGGCCAGUUUCUCAGUUUCCUUUGGGCCUGCCUUUAUUUUGAUAGUCGCAGAAUGCAGGUUCAGAUGCGAUCCGGUGCAUUCUGGGUGGUAUCCCCAUAGACAGAAUACAAGUUCAAGACUCAUUUUUAUGUCCAUUUUUAUAGUGGUAGACUGUAUGUAAUAGACCAGAUGGUUCAUUCCAAAUACAUGACUUGGUCUUACUGCUAUAUAUGAAGGAAGUUUGAAAAUGUAAUGGGGACAAAAGCCGUGCGUGACUUCGGUAUACCCAGACUUCAUUCAGAUUUCUUAAAAAUCUGCUAGGGAUGUCUGUUGACCAGACGUUGGAAAACCUUUGGUGUCAGGGAGAGUAGAGGAGAAGUUCUGAUUUUCAUAACCCUGGUUUCUUAUCUAGGCCUGUUUCCUUGCGUGAAAACAUACAUCACCAAGUAAUUUGUAGUACAAAGAACAAGAGAAGAAACCCUAAGAAGAUAGCUUAUUUGUUAUCCUCCCUUUUAAUGACUAACCUUAAUCCAAAUGAAUCCACUGAGAACCAGCCUGUGGAUGCCUACUGGGCUUUCACCCUGGACCAGGAAUUUUUGACGUAUGCCUGUGUUGAAGGCACUGGAUGCUUGUUUUGUGGAAGACAUGUUCAUUGAGGUAAGUGGCUCAUCGCUUGGUGUGUUUGGCUCUCUUUGGCAUUAUGCAUAGCCAAGGUCCCAGAUUUUGGCUGCUCUCAGUGGGUGUUCUUGCAUCAGAACUUUAAAAAAAAUAACACUACCUUAACACUGAGACUGUCAGGUAUUUGUCAGUAUUUAUUUCUAAUUUCCUACUUUAAAUCUUAGGAGACAAAGUGUUUCUCCAACUGGACGCUGAUUUGAAACACAACUAGAAUGCUACAGGUCUCUCUUCCAGUAUGCAGCUGCUGUACCUGAAAAUUUUUCCCCAUAAUUUCCCAUCUUUAGGGUAUGUCCCUGUUAUCAGGUGUGGAAUUAAUGUGGGUAAAUUUCCAUUUCAGUUGAAUUUCCUGUCAUCCCCAGCAAAACCUGUGAAUCCUUCUUCAAAGCAUAGAGGAGGCAGAGACAAGUCUUAAACCGGCUUCCCUUCGCUUUUACCAGGUAGCCUGGUUCAGUCCCAGCUGGGUCCUGAAGGAGCACAGUACUAGAGCCUGAGUCAUGUUGACUAUUAAUAAAGUGCAUUAAGUUUGGGUCAGGCAAAGUGGUGGCAAAAGUUCAUGAUGCAGGACAGAGGAAACAAGUGGACAAGACAAGUGGAGCCCAGCUCUGUUCGCAUGGGAGGCCGGGCGAUGCUGGCAUGGGUGUGGUUGGCCGAGUUCUCAUAGCUAGAGAAAGGCCGUGUAGGUAUAAGUGCUUAAUGUUUCAUCUGUCUGAAAGACCAGCUAUUUGAUAAUCUUCCCGAUUAAAUUUCUAAAAUUGCUACUUUGGGAAUUUUUUUCUUUAUUCUUGUAAAGUUUUGCUUCCAUUAUAUACUCAUUCAUUAGUCAGUGUACUUGCCCCUGAAUUCCAUAUCUGAAACUGCAGUCACGGGAGAUUCAGAGCCAAGGGCAAAAUAAAGUGGCAGGCACUGGGUGUGUGUGGUAGUUCUGCACUAGGGUGGCCAGGAAGCAGCCAAGCAGGUGUGCCGGGCAGGGAGUUGUUAAUGAACACCCAGGCAAGAGGACGGGCCUGAGCCUGAGUGUGGCCAGCAGAAAGUGUUGAGUUGCUUAAAAGAGACCCUGGGAGGAUGAAUUUGGAAUCAUCAUCCACUCACUGUUGGACAGAAAGACUGCAGAGAAGGGCACUGCUGGGGUGGGGUUUGUUAACUCCCUCUGAAAUGAAAGAAAAUACCUCUAGUGGCAUGAAACGGCUAAGUUUUUUUUAAUGUUACUUCUUUAAUUUUAGAGACGGUGUCUGGCUUUGUCACGCAAGCUGGAGUUUGGUGGUGUGAUUGCAGCUCACUGCAGCCUUAAACAACUGGGCUAGGUGAUCCUCCCAUCUCAGCCUCCCAAGUAGCUGGGACUACCUGUGCACACCACCAUGCCUGGCUGUUUUUAAUACGGGGUUUUGCUGAGUUGCUCAGGCGCUCCUCAAACUGCUGGCCUCAAGUGAUCCUCCAGCCUGGGCCUCUCAAACAUAAAUAGGCUGGGCGUGGUGGCUCACGUCUGUAAAGAUUUAAAGCGGAAAAGCGGAAUGCAGUGAAAUAGCAUGAGAAAGAGCGUUUUUAUGUACAUCACAGACAAGCCUUGUUCUGCUGAAGAGGUGAUGCCACGAGGUGGGGAGGAGCUCACUUCAGGCACCACUCCCACUUCCAUUGCCCGCAAAUCCAGGAAAGAAAUGACUAAUGAACUCUAGUGAUCGCAAACUGCUCAAUCGGUACUCAUCAAUUUAAAAUGACUGUCCAGCCUUGCUGCACACUAAACUCAUCUGUAGAACUUUAUAAAACCACGGAUGACCAUCACACUAGCAGGAUUUUAGAUUCAGAGUUGGGGUGGGGCCUGGAGCUCUGUUUUCUGAAACUUUGCGGGCCAUUCUGAACCUGCAGCCAGGCAGGACUCUGGCAAGAAGAGGCGUGUGGCUAAUAUGACGGAAGUCUGAAUCCAAGGACUUUUUUUUUUUUUUUUUUUGGAGACAGUCUUGCUUUGUCUCCCAGGUUGGUGUGCAGGGGUGUGAUCUCGGCUCACUGCAACCUCCAUUUCCCAGAUUCAAGCGAUUCUCGUGCCUCAGCCUUUCAAGUAGCUGGGAUUACAGGUGCACACCACCACACCCAGCUAAUAGUAUUUUUGAUAGAGAGGGGGUUUCGCAAUGUUGGCCAGGCUGGUCUUGAACUCCCGACUUCAAGCUAUCCACCUGCCUCGGCCUCCCAAAGUGCUGGGAUUACAGGCGUGAGCUACUUCACCCAGCCCCAAGAACAUCUUGAAAUGGAGUUUGAUUACCAAAGUUUACAUAGAGUAAUGGAUAAUUAAAAUUUUCAAUUUAUGGUGCAUUACAAAAUGUUAUAAACAAGCCUCCGGGAAAGGCAGAAAUUGCCAGAUGUAAGUAUAUAAAACUUACACAGUUUGUUCCUUUUUGUUGUCUUCCCUUGUGGAGAUGGGUCAGUGUAACAUCCUAUUCAUUAAUAGCUCUCAGAUGUCCCAUGAGAAUGGCACAUGUUAUUUCCCAACAGUGGGAAUGGAAUUAGUUCCUUUAUAUCUCAGUCUCAUCUGGUCUUGUAAGCCGGUGAAGGGUUUCCCAGGGCACCAGCCACCAGCUCUGUAUAGUAGUUACAGUUUCCCUCUCUAGAAUCCCAAAGAGGUUCAGAUCCCACUGCUCCUCUCAUUGGCUUCGUGACCCUGGGUACGCUGCUCAACUUGCGCAAGGAUUACUGUCCGCUUUGUACAAUGGAGAUACCUAUAGUGUCCACUUAGGAGAUGCUGUGCAUGCCUCAGUGAGGUAAUGUCCGCAGAAAGCACAAUGCCUAGUAUGUAGAAAGUGUCCGAUAAAUAUAAUAUGCGGCUAAACAGCGGAGUCCACAGCCUGAAUGGAACUUCUUUUUCUACGUAAAUACAGCAAACAAUGCAGGGAAAUGAGGUGGACAGUGUUCUCCGUGGAGGGCUAAACAGCAUUGCUUUCCAGCUGACUUUUAUUUUUGGAGUCUGGGACUAGGUGUUAACAUUCCUUUACUAGUUGGUUUUGCAUACCGCACAGUCCCUGCAUCUAUUUAAGAGUUUUGAGGUUUGUUGUGGGAAGUUUUUUUUUUUUUUUUUUUUUUUGAGGCGGAGUCUCGCUCUGUCGCCCAGGCUGGAGUGCAGUGGCGCGAUCUCGGCUCACUGCAAGCUCCGCCUCCUGGGUUCACGCCAUUCGCCUGCCUCAGCCUCCAGAGUAGCUGGGACUACUGGCGCCCGCCACCACGCCCGGCUAAUUUUUUUUGUGUAUUUUUAGUAGAGAUGGGGUUUCACCAUGUUAGGCAGGAUGGUCUCAGUCUCCUGACCUUGUGAUCCAUCUGCCUUGGCCUCCCAAAGUGCUGGGAUUACAGGUGUGAGGGAGUUUUUCGGUAGUUUGCUUUGCCUUGAUAAACUAUAUGAUAUUUAAAUGUUUUAUAAGGAUGGGUUUUCAGUAGAAUUUCUCUGUACAACCUCAGGGAGACUGCCUGGAGGAAUAACUGUGGUAAGGGUCUGUUUUUGAACAGGCAUGGUCAUUAGACCCUUGUGAUCACGCAUCCAGGGGCCAGUCCCCACCCUUUGCUCCCACUCCAAGGAAAGUCUGUUACAUUUUUAGCCUUCAGAGGUUUGAUGUAGAUAGGAAGAGAUGAGGGUGACAGAAAUCAGCUCUUAAGUUUAUAAAUAAAACAGGGAUAUUAUCGGGGAAGCUUUUGAAAUGUAAUAGGUUGUAACCCACAUUUUGAAAGCAGUAAGGAAAUAAUUGCUGCUUUUUUCUUCUUCUUUAUUCUGUUGACUUUGUUGAUAAUAUUAGGUGACUACAUCGAGCCUGGGUUCUCUCAGUAUUAGCCUGUUAUUCCUAAAGUAUCAUCCUCUCCUUGUAUCAAAUAUAAGGACAAAAAUGUCUUAGGAUAAAAGUCUGUUUGUUUGCAUUAGACUAUACAUGAUUUGCAUUACAAUGGGCCGUGGAUUUGGAUGGAUGAUGAAGCUGAAACAAGGGACCUAAUCAUGGGAUUUAACUGUUCACUUCAGGUAGAUAAGAUAUUUCUGGGAGAAGUAAAUUGGAUGAGCUUUUGUGCUUCCCAGCAGCUCCAGGUCUUGUCCCUGGCCAGUCUGGGCAGCUCUGCGCUCAGAGGCCUUUGGCACGAUGGGUCCUCCCAGCAGGGGCUCCAGCGCUCACCGCUGGGUGAGAUCUACAGGGCUCAGUGCGCUUGGAGUCCUGGAUUCCUCCAGGACUGCUACUGUAUUCCAAUUGAGUGGUGGUUUGCUCUUCACAGAGCGCUUACAUGGGAUUCUUACCUUCUGACUGGAGUGUCACCCUCGCCCAGGAAUGUGGGUGCUGGAGAGACGGGCUACCUCUUUCUGUAGGCGGAUGUUUCUGAAGGCAUCUCCCACUGAUUAUGUAAUGACAGCUACUUAACAUCUUCUGUAGUCUUGAAGAAUUCAGAUGAGGAGCUUGUCCAGGGAGGGCUCCCACGUGCGUAUUCACUAAUUGUGGUCUUUCUCCCCAGCUCGGUUUUGUUUGCGUAUUAGAGUUCUGACCAUCUUCACUAGAAGUGGGGGCGGCUAGCAGUGACUAGAUGCAAGAAGCAAAACGGUAAAUUUCCUUUUACUGGCAAAAUUAAAACAGUGAACUUGAAAUAUCUCCCCUACUCCCUGCAGAGACACUCUGAAUCAAAGAAAACAAUCAGUACUAACCCUGGAAACAAUUUAAAAAUGAACAAAAAGUCCUACCCUGAAGAAGAAGAAUGUCUUACCAGCAAACGGUCUUGGGACAGCUGGUGUGAGAACUAUAUAAGAGAAAUCAACAAAUAUUAAUUGAACACCAGUCAUGUGCAAAGCACUUAGCUAGGUCUUAGGGAUGAGGACAAAAAGCAUGUCACAUUUUGUUGUUAUAAGUGGGAAAGAUAAGUAAUUACAAGUAAGCCCAGUGUUUUUAAAAGAGUGUGAACAGAGACCUUAUUCUAAUCCAGAGAGGCUGUGAAGUGCUGUAUUCCCAAGGAACUGAAGUUCUAGCUGAUACCUAAUGGAGGAAUGGGUGUUAUCCUGGUGGGAAUGCCCUAGAAUCUAGGAGAAGACAACAGGCCAUUCGAAGGUGAGGAGGCUUGCCAGCAUCAGUUUAUAAGUGGACAGAGUCGAGAGCUAUUUAGGAAGGAGAGCUGACAGACCUCGGGGACUGAAUGGAUGCUGGGAGUAGGGGUGAAAAGAGAGGAGUCAGGCUUCCUCCCAGAGUUUGAGGACUUUGAGUGCUAAGGGCUUGUAGGAGAACGUUGUGGAGAUGUCCGGUAGGCAUCUGAAAGAAUGGAUGGAGGAGGGGAAAGUCGGGCCUGGGAAUGGCCAAUUUCUGGUCAUUCUCAUAUAGGCAACUGAUGGCGAAGGGGAUGACCUAGAGGGAGUUGGGAGGACAGCCUAGGAUACGUAAAUAAGAGAAUCUUGUAUGUUCUAAAAAUUAACAUCAUUGCAGCUUCCUCAGCCCUAGGAUGGUUUUUAGAUCUAUCAAGGGAUAGAAGAUUGUCCAGCCCCUUGCUGCCCAGUGUAGUCAGUGGGCUGACGACAUUAGCAUCACCUGGGUGCUUGCUAGCAAUGCAAAAUCUCAGGCCCCAGCCCAGACCACUGGAUGAGAAUCUGCAUUUGAACAAGGUCCCCAGGUCAUUCAUGCACAUUCAAAGUCAGAGACACUGCCCCAACACCUCACUUUAGAGUGAGAAAACUUAACAGGUUUAAGCAACUUGCAGAAGAUGACACAACUGACCAGCGACAGUCUGUCUUCUAGUCAGGCCUCUUUCCAGUUCUCCACGCUGACCUUGACUUUCGAGAUCACAUACCAAGACCUUCAGCUGGAUGGUCCCUGUAGCUGCUGUGACCACUAGAAGCAGGGUUAGGGGCGAGACUAAUUUAAUAUCAAUUAAUGUAGACACUAGGCUUAGGGCUAGGGAAAAUGUAGUGAAGGAUGCCUGUAUUGUCCUAAUGAACCACACUGGUGCCUACAAAAUUUUUAUUUUGGCAAAACCGUCCAUGAAUUUGGAGAUGUUGAACAGGUUUCUCUCCGACAAUCGUCUCGUUUAAUUGUGAAACUAGAAUCACUUCCAGGAAGCUCUGAAGAAUCAAGUCUGAGUGAUGCAAUGCUGCUUCCUCCUUCCUUCUCAAAAGCCUGCUCUUUGCCCAUUUCUCUGUUCCCAAGGUCAUUUUCUCCCCUUCUUGUUUCCAGGAUCCACAGUUCCUGCUCUGCUUCCGCUUUCCCCACUGCUGGUUCAGGCUGUCUGCAGCAGCAGCAGCUCCAGGGUGCUGGGACACUGCUGGGUGACGCUCCACAGUGUGUGCUUCCCCAUGUGGCUUCCACAGUCCCCUCUUGCUUCUCCCACAUGUUAGUCUUCAUAGAUUAGUCUUCAUCAAUUCUUAGUAUUAUUUUUUAGGGAUAGGGUCUUGCUGUGUUGCCCAGGCUGCAGUGCAGUGGUAUGAUCUCUGCUUACUGCAGCCUCCACCUCUGGGACUCAGGCGAUCCUCCUGCCUCAGCCUCCCAAGUAGCUGGGACCACAGGCGCAUGCCACUGUGCCUGGCUAAAUUAUUUUAUAUUUUGUAGAGUUGAGGUCGCACUUUUUUGCCCAUGCUGGUCUUGAACCCCUGGGCUCAAGCGAUCCUUCUGCCUCAGCCUCCCAUUACGGGCAGGAGCCACUGCACACAGCUGAUGAAUUUUCGUUUAGGCCCCUUUCUUUGUGAGAGGGGGCCCCAGGAUUAUGCCCCGGGAUUAAAAGAAGCUGGGAGGCUCUCCAGGACCCUGAACAAAGGUGGAAGUAGGGUUGUAAAUGGAAGAAAAAAUAAGAGAGAUUCAUUAUGUUCUAAUGACUAUGAGGGAAGCUUUAGUUUUUGUCUCCCUGAAGCAUCAACCUGCUUUCCUGCUGCUGUUAUCACAUCCUUCCAGGGCUAUCGGCUGUUCAGGAACAGGAGAGCUCUGGAAGAGCAGGGACGACUUUGGCUUCUGUUUCCUGCCCAUUGCAGAUUAGGCAUCAGCAAGGUACCCUCCUGUUUUUGUAUGGCUCACCAAACUAAGGGUGAUUUUCACAUUUUACAUGGCUGAAAAACAUCAAAUGAUAUUUCAGGACAUAGGGAAAUUAUAUGACAUUUGAAUUUCAGUGUCCAUAAAUGAAGUUUUAUUGGAACAUAACCACAUUCAUUUGCAAGUUGUCCACGGCCACUUUGGUGCUACUGUGGCAGAAUUGAGUAGUUGCUGCAGAGACCGUAUGAUGAGAAUAUGUGGCAUUCUCAUCAUUUUGCCCUGCCGCUCUGUGCAAUGUAAAUUGCAGUGACACAGUUAUAACUCAGCAGCAUUUUGAAUGCCACUUGUAUUCCCAUGCUACAACAUUUUAUUUUUUAUUACCAAUAUAUACAAGAAAAGUGGAUUUCAAAUAUCAUUGUGCUUUUAAGGUACAAUGGAGUAUGAAUUGUUACUGAAUUAGGCAGCAAAGUGCAAUGACAUGGUAGCUGUCCUAAGGAACACAAUACAACCAGGUGCAGUGGCUCAUGCCUGUAAUCCCAACGAUUUGGGUGGCUGAGGUGGGAGAAUCACUUGAACCCAGGAUUUGGAGACCAGCUUGGGUGGUAUAGUGAGACCCCCCAUCUCCACAAAAAGUAAAAAAAAACCAAAAUACAUGUUGUUACUUCCCAUCUUAGCACUCAUCAAGAUAUUUCUAAUUCACAAGAAAGCAAUGGUCAGAAAAAUUAGAAAAUUUAAAAUUGAAUAUCUCAUCACAGAAUUUAUUCACAAAAAUAAAAAAUGAAAAUGAAGCUACAACCAAAGUAAGUUUCAGAUGGCUCAUUUGUUAGCCAAGCAAGGAAAGUCACUUAUGGUGAAUUAAUUAAAUCAUGCUUGAUUACUGCAGCUGAAGAAACAUGCUCAGAGAAAGUAAACUUGUUUAUUGGCCUUUCCACGACAACAGUUGCUCAAAGAGUUGACAUUAGGAAUGACAUCAGUAGUCGACUAAAAAGGCAAAUGGUUUUGAGUGGUUUCCCCUGACUCUCAUGACAGGGGUCACCAUAUGUUAUGCACACUGCUCCGCUAUUGCUCUUUAUUUGAGGAGCCAGUACCAAGUUGGAAGUAACUGAAGAAUUGGCCUCUAUCAAUAGUCUUAUGUGGAACAACUACUGGCAAAAGUAUUUUCAAAGCUGAGAAAACUGGUCAGGUGUGGCGGCUCAUGCCUAUAGUCCCAACACUUUGGGAGGCCAAGGUGGGCAGAUCACCUGAGGUCAGGAGUUUGAGACCUGCCUGGCCAACAUGGUGAAACUACAUCUCUACUAAAAGUACAAAAAUUAGCCGGGCAUGAUGGCAUGCACUGGUAAUUCCAGCUACUCAGGAGGCUGAGGCAGGAGAAUCGCUUGAACCCAGGAGGUGGAGGUUGCAGUGAGCUGAGAUUGCACCACUGUACUCCAGCCUGGAUGACAGAGUGAGAACAUUGUCUCAAAACAAAAAGUUGAGAAAACGAAUUCAGUACACCCUGAAGUGGAAUCUGCUAAGAUGUGUUAUGACUGUUGGUAGUGGAAAUAUAUGUGUGUAUUAGUCCAUUUUCAUACUGCUAUAAAGAAAAGCCUGAGACUGGGUAAUUUAUAAAGAAAAAGAGGUUUAAUGGACUCACAGUCCCGCAUGGUUGGGGAGGCCUCACAAUCGUUGUGGAAGGUAAAGGAGAAGCCAAGGCAAGUCUUAGGUGGCGGCAAGCAAGAGAGUGUGUGCAGGGGAACUGCCCUUUAUAAAACCAUCAGAUCUCAUGAGACUUACUCACUAUUAUGAGAACAGCAUGGUAAAAUCCUGCCUCCAUGAUUCAGUUACCUCCCACUGGGUCCUACCCAUGACACGUGGGGAUUAUGGGGGCUACAAUUCAAUGAGAUUUGGGUGGGGACACAGCUAACUCAUAUCAGUGUGGAAUAGAAAAUGGCUCAGUUGGACAACUUACAAAGCUUGUAAUAAUAUAAGGUGUUAAAGCCUAUAGAUUAUUCAUUGUAUUAUUUAAGUCAACAGAUACUUUGUGAGAAAUAUUUGAAUCUAUCAUGCAUUAUUGAACCAGUAUUGUCAAUAGUGAACUUCCUUUAGCUCUUGUGGACUUCACUAUCAACAGCUCUCAUGAAUUUUUGUCAGAAAUAUUAGCUGAAUAUCCCGACAUGGCCUGUAAUACAGCAGUUCAAUGGUUUAGUAGUGGUAAAGUUUCAUUUAAGUUUUGAGCUCAGGACAAAGAUUGAAAUUUUUCUGAAUGAGAACUGCCCCGAACCACCGUUACUAAACACUGAAUAGUUUUGGAAAUUCACUUUUGCUGCAGACUUGAUAGUGUUUCUUAAGGAAUUCAGCCUAAACCACAAGAUAAAAACAGUGUUUAUGUGAAACUCCUACUGUGUUAAGUGAUUUCAAGAAGAACUAUUGUUUGAAUCACAACUAAUGUUACUGCUUUAAGCUCUUCCCAUGUUGUUAAAAGUUAAAAAAAGAAGAGCUCCAUUCCCACACACAUUUGCCACAGAUACAUUAUCUGAGCCCAAACUACAGUUUGAGCAGUGUGUUAGGGACCUCAAUGCAAACCCAAAAGAAAUUUUUAUAUUUCAGAAUCCAUUGAUCUGCAUUUGAGAAGUGAUUAAUGUGUUGAAAGGCAACUAUCUAAAGAAAAAUUUAAUAGAGUCUAAUAGAAUCUUAUAAAAAUGUAUAAAUGUGUUUUAUGUAAUAAAUAUGCUAAGCUAAA